AAAUCCGGCCCAGGAUGUAGAGCUGGCAGUGCCUGACGGCGCGUCUGACGCGGAGUUGGGUGGGGUAGAGAGUAGGGGGCGGUAGUCGGGGGUGGUGGGAGAAGGAGGAGGCGGCGAAUCACUUAUAAAUGGCGCCGAAGCAGGACCCGAAGCCUAAAUUCCAGGAGGGUGAGUGUGCGCCUUUGGGAAAAAGGCACCUAACGGCGCAGGAGAUAGAGGCGGGCUCGAGGUGAUUGAGGCUUGAGGGCCGGGGGCGGCGCGGGCUGCGCCCUGAGAAGGCGGCGGUCAGUGCUUUGUGCGGGGAAAGCGCAUUGCGGAUGGCAAUUCCGGUGAGCGAGUGCUGUGCUUUCAUGGGCCUCUUCUUUAUGAAGCAAAGUGUGUAAAGGUUGCCAUAAAGGACAAACAAGUGAAAUACUUCAUACAUUACAGUGGUUGGAAUAAAAAUUGGGAUGAAUGGGUUCCGGAGAGCAGAGUACUCAAAUACGUGGACACCAAUUUGCAGAAACAGCGAGAACUUCAAAAAGCCAAUCAGGAGCAGUAUGCAGAGGGGAAGAUGAGAGGGGCUGCCCCAGGAAAGAAGACAUCUGGUCUGCAACAGAAAAAUGUUGAAGUGAAAACGAAAAAGAACAAACAGAAAACACCUGGAAAUGGAGAUGGUGGCAGUACCAGUGAGACCCCUCAGCCUCCUCGGAAGAAAAGGGCCCGGGUAGAUCCUACUGUUGAAAAUGAGGAAACAUUCAUGAACAGAGUUGAAGUUAAAGUAAAGAUUCCUGAAGAGCUAAAACCGUGGCUUGUUGAUGACUGGGACUUAAUUACCAGGCAAAAACAGCUCUUUUAUCUUCCUGCCAAGAAGAAUGUGGAUUCCAUUCUUGAGGAUUAUGCAAAUUACAAGAAAUCUCGUGGAAACACAGAUAAUAAGGAGUAUGCGGUUAAUGAAGUUGUGGCAGGGAUAAAAGAAUACUUCAACGUAAUGUUGGGUACCCAGCUACUCUAUAAAUUUGAGAGACCACAGUAUGCUGAAAUUCUUGCAGAUCAUCCCGAUGCACCCAUGUCCCAGGUGUAUGGAGCGCCACAUCUCCUGAGAUUAUUUGUACGAAUUGGAGCAAUGUUGGCUUAUACACCUCUGGAUGAGAAGAGCCUUGCUUUAUUACUCAAUUAUCUUCACGAUUUCCUAAAGUACCUGGCAAAGAAUUCUGCAACUUUGUUCAGUGCCAGCGAUUAUGAAGUGGCUCCUCCUGAGUACCAUCGGAAAGCUGUGUGAGAGGCACUCUCACUCACUUAUGUUUGGAUCUCCGUAAACACAUUUUUGUUCUUAGUCUAUCUCUUGUACAAACGAUGUGCUUUGAAGAUGUUAGUGUAUAACAAUUGAUGUUUGUUUUCUGUUUGAUUUUAAACAGAGAAAAAAUAAAAGGGGGUAAUAGCUCCUUUUUUCUUCUUUCUUUUUUUUUUUCAUUUCAAAAUUGCUGCCAGUGUUUUCAAUGAUGGACAACAGAGGGAUAUGCUGUAGAGUGUUUUAUUGCCUAGUUGACAAAGCUGCUUUUGAAUGCUGGUGGUUCUAUUCCUUUGACACUACGCACUUUUAUAAUACAUGUUAAUGCUAUAUGACAAAAUGCUCUGAUUCCUAGUGCCAAAGGUUCAAUUCAGUGUAUAUAACUGAACACACUCAUCCAUUUGUGCUUUUGUUUUUUUUUAUGGUGCUUAAAGUAAAGAGCCCAUCCUUUGCAAGUCAUCCAUGUUGUUACUUAGGCAUUUUAUCUUGGCUCAAAUUGUUGAAGAAUGGUGGCUUGUUUCAUGGUUUUUGUAUUUGUGUCUAAUGCACGUUUUAACAUGAUAGACGCAAUGCAUUGUGUAGCUAGUUUUCUGGAAAAGUCAAUCUUUUAGGAAUUGUUUUUCAGAUCUUCAAUAAAUUUUUUCUUUAAAUUUCAAAGAACAAUGUGCUUGUGUUGAUGCCUUACAAAAACCAUUGUAUAUUUGUGUAUUCCUUCUUGUAUUUAGACAGUGGUUUUUCAGGUGCGUGCUUUGUUUUCUGGUAUGGCCUUUAUGGAAUGAGACGCUUUAGCUUUGGUACGUAGCGCUAAUCCAUAGCAGCUUUGGCAGUUUGCUGUCUUGAGUCUUAGCUAAAAAGUUAGAAGUUUACAUGACUGUUUUUUUUAUUUUCCCUAAAUUAUUACUUACUCUGAGCAUUAAUUAAGGGCAUUUUCACCUGUGUAAAAUUAUGGUCAGCUUUUUUCUGUCUAUAAUUGUUUACUUUUGUGGGUUUACUCUAGAAACAUGAGCCAAAAAUGUCAAUAGACAACACAGUAUUAAAAUAACCCAAAAGUUGUAAAGGGCAA